UCUUUCUCUACAGAUUCCCCUUCAGUACUUGAAGGUGGAAUAAUCCACCUGAAACUGGCAAUACAAAACUUGCACCUAAACAGUGUGCUGCAAAGGAAAUAGGAUGCUUCUGCCGCACUGGUUUUCUGAAUAAUUAGAUCAAGUUUUGUGUUAGAAGUGUCCUAAUAAACCUGAAGGGCCUGCAAAAGUGGCUGACUCUUUUUUUUUUUUUUUUUUUUUGGACAGGGUCGUUGUGUUGCUCAGGAUGGAGUGCAGUGGUAAAAUCACGGCUCACUGCAGCCUUGACCUCCUGGGUUCAAGAAAUCCUCCUGCCUCAGCCUCCUGAGCAGCUGGAACCACAGGUAUAAGCCAACAUGCCCAGCUAAUUUUUUGUAUUUUUUGUAGAGACGGGGUUUCGCCAUGUUGCCCGGGCUUGACUGUGGCUUUUAAUCUCCUCUACUCACCACUACAAUCUGGAAAAGUGAAAACAUAUAUAUUAUUUCUGUACUACAUUUUCUGUUAACUGGAAACCAAUCCUAGAAAAUCUUGGUGCAGAAUUACAUAUUUUGACAUAUUGAAAAAUAUGAUAAUAAUAUAGCUACAAAGGUGUGAUUUUUACAGACAGCCUGAAAUAGUACCUUUUACCAGAAAAUAUCGCCAAAUACAUCUACUGUGACAUCACCAAAACUGUGAACAAGACCUAAGGAGGGAACUUCAAGGGCUCUCACCUUUCUUAUUGGAGAAAGCAAGGUUGUCUAACAAAGAGAAUGGAAGAGGCCAUCCUACUCAAUCAAACUUCUUUAGUGACAUAUUUUCGGCUUAGAGGUUUAUCUGUAAAUCAUAAGGCACGGAUAGCUAUGUUUUCCAUGUUCCUCAUUUUUUAUGUCCUGACACUGAUUGGGAAUGUUCUCAUUGUCAUAACUAUUAUCUAUGACCACCGGCUCCAUACUCCCAUGUAUUUCUUCCUCAGCAACCUGUCCUUUAUUGAUGUCUGCCACUCCACUGUCACUGUCCCCAAGAUGCUGAGAGACGUGUGGUCAGAGGAAAAGCUCAUCUCUUUUGAUGCCUGUGUGACCCAGAUGUUCUUCCUGCACCUCUUUGCCUGCACAGAGAUCUUCCUCCUCACCGUCAUGGCCUAUGAUCGGUAUGUGGCCAUCUGUAAACCCCUGCAGUACAUGAUAGUGAUGAACUGGAAGGUAUGUGUGCUGCUGGCUGUGGCCCUCUGGACAGGAGGGACCAUCCACUCCAUAGCCCUCACCUCCCUUACCAUCAAGCUGCCCUACUGUGGUCCUGAUGAGAUUGACAACUUCUUCUGUGAUGUACCUCAGGUGAUCAAGCUGGCCUGCAUUGACACCCACGUCAUUGAGAUCCUCAUUGUCUCCAACAGUGGAUUGAUCUCCGUGGUCUGUUUUGUGGUCCUGGUGGUGUCCUACGCAGUCAUCCUGGUGAGUCUGAGGCAGCAGAUCUCCAAGGGCAAGCGGAAGGCCCUGUCCACCUGUGCAGCCCAUCUCACUGUAGUUACACUGUUCCUGGGACACUGCAUCUUCAUCUAUUCCCGCCCAUCCACCAGCCUCCCAGAGGACAAGGUAGUAUCUGUGUUUUUCACUGCAGUCACCCCCCUGCUGAACCCCAUUAUCUAUACCCUUAGGAAUGAAGAAAUGAAGAGUGCCUUAAACAAGUUAGUGGGGAGAAAAGAGAGAAAAGAAGAAAAAUGAAAAUGUCUACGUCCUUAGGAUACGUGGUGCUCCAAAUUAAAGAAGCGCCUUGCAAAGAAUAAGUUACAUACCAUAUUUAUCAGACUAUGUGACUUAUAAAACUAUCCUUGGUCCAAUAUCUGACAGUCAUAGCAAUCGUUAUGGUUAUUAAUAUCUUCUCUGUGCUGGAAAUUAUUCUAGGCACUGUGCAUUUACUUAAUUCUCACAACUUUGAAAGGUAGAUAUUAUGAUGCUUGUUUGUACAUGAAGAAACUAAAGCUCGAGGAGAGUAAAUAACAUGCCCAAAGUCACUCAGCUAGAAAACAAUGAAGGCAGCAUGUGAAUCCAAGUGGAUCAACAGAAACUCAAGCUCUUUUCACAACAUAUGCUGCCUCUUUCUGCUUUUCUGUUGGAGUGAUAACCAAGGUCUAAACAAACCUUCAGAUUUCUGGGCAGCCCUUGCCUGCAUCAUUCACUCAGAUGCUUAUGUAAACAGCUUAGCAAACACUAGUGAAGCAGAUAAAGUGAGUUUCCACAUGACUUUGGUGACAGAGAAAGAAGACUUUGAACAGGUGAAGUUACUGACACUCUCAAGUAUCCAGGCAAAAUCUGCCAUCAGAGCAAUGAAAUGGGGAUAUCUUACUAUUCAUUCAUUUGACAAAUAUUUACUGAGCACUUAUUAUGUACCAGAUACUAGGUUUAUAGCCAUAAAUAAGACAUACAUGUAGUCCUUCCUUCAUGGAGUUUAGGGUCUAGUGAAAAUAGAAAACAAAAAUAUGAACAAAUAAAUUUUAACUACAGAUUGUGAUAAAUGCUAUAAAACAGCAGGGUGCUGUUAGAGAGUAUGGAAGAGACUUGCUUUAGUGGUCAAGGAUGGCCUCUCUGAGGAAGUUACAUUUAAGAUUAAAAGGAGCCAGCCAUAAGAGAGGUGAUGGACAUUCUAGACAGGGGAAAUGGCCGGUGCAAAGAUCUAUGCUGGGAAAGACCUUGGCUUGUUCAAGGAAGUAAAUGAUCAGUGUGAUUACAGCUUAGACUAUAAGGCAGAGAGUGGCAAGAGAGUGAUAUCAGAGAGCUAAAAAGAAUCUUUCCAUAUUCUCUCAAGAAGUUUAGAAUCUUUUCCAGUACAAUAAGAAGCCACCAGAAUGAUUUAAGCACAGGUGUGGCAUGAAAUAAUUUAUGUUUUAAUAAAAUUAUUUUAGUUAUUAUGUAGAGAAUUCACUCAACUAAGCAACAGCAUCCAAUAUUGUUCUUAGAGCAAUGGAUGACUGUUAAGUACUUAGUCAUAAAUACUUAGAAAACAACUUGGUAGAAACUUGGUAGAAAACACCAAGUUGGAUAAACCAUUGUCUAUAAACCAACAUCUUAAAUCUCACUGUGGCGGCACAUAGUGUAGCAGAAUGGAAUGUGGUGAAUCAACUGGGAUAUGAAGAGGAUAUCCCAGAUAACGGCAUCUCAUAUUCAUGUUUACAAAAGAGCAUGACACAUUGGAAAUCAUCAGUUUGUUCUCACAUCAUCGCUAAAAAAGGCAUGCUUAAAUGCAGCUGGGAUUUCCUAGGCACUCAGUGAGUGUAUGAUCAAUAAACCUGUGAGCCACAAGGUCUACAUCAUGAUUUUUAGGAGGAAAAUUUUUAUUUGCUAGGAAAUGUGUUAGGAAGGAUAUUCAAGUGACACAAGAAUUAUAAAAUUUAUGUAAAAUAAAUGCCCUUUUAUUAUAGGCAAUGGCAGACAAUAAGGAGAAAUAUCUAAAUAUCUUUCCAAUGAGCCCAAAUGGAACUGCUUGUGCAGGAAUCAGCCAUACAGAGGAACACGUGCAAAAUUGUCAUAUUGUCUGUCAACAACACAAUGCUUCAACGUAGCCAUUAAGAUUGUAGCUGGUAAAACUAUAACGGAACAACGUUGUGAUGUUUGCUUAUUUUUUUCAUAGCAGCAAGCAAAAUUUCUGACACUACCCGUUUUUAGUCACACUAAUUUUUCAACUCUCUGGGGACGUAAAAAUAAAACAUUUUGUCUCCGUUUUACAGAAAAAAGCUUUUCAGACUCAGAGACAAGAUAAAAAUGUAUUUAAUUACUCACUAAAUAAAUAGAGAGUCUUAAAGAACAAAAAUAAAAGAUCUUGAUGCUUG